AUUCCACAGACUUUCGCUCCCUAGCAGCGGGUCGGAGAUCGAAGGAACGGGCCAAUUGCGGCUGAAACGUCUUUGGAAGGAGGAAGGGGGUGAGGGAGCAUCCCUUUGAGUUUCGCCUCUUCUCGAGGCGGUGGUGGGAAGGGAGACAUACUUAAUACUGCCCUCUUAAUCCAACGGACCUUACAUCGUGUAGACUGCCGGGAGGGCGGCGGGAAAAGGGCAAGACGGGAGUUGGGGAAGGGAAGGAGCCAGGAAGCCGCGCGGGAGGGCGCGCGCGCGCGCCCCUUUUUCAGCAGUGUGGCGGGGUCGCACGCACGCCCGCCUCGGCGGCUGGGCGCGAUUUGCGACAGUGGGGGGGGCGGUGGAGGUGGCGGCGGCAGCGGCAACUUUGCGGCAAGCUCGGGCCGGGCUUGCUUGACGGCGGUGUGGCGGAGGCCCCGCCCCAGGCGGCAGGAACCUGGAGGGAGGCGGAGGAAUAUGUCCGAGAGGGAAGUGUCGACUGCGCCGGCGGGAACAGACAUGCCUGCGGCCAAGAAGCAGAAGCUGAGCAGUGACGAGAACAGCAAUCCAGACCUCUCUGGAGACGAGAAUGAUGACGCUGUCAGUAUAGAAAGUGGUACAAACACUGAACGCCCUGAUACACCUACAAACACGCCAAAUGCACCUGGAAGGAAAAGUUGGGGAAAGGGAAAAUGGAAGUCAAAGAAAUGCAAAUAUUCUUUCAAAUGUGUAAAUAGUCUCAAGGAAGAUCAUAACCAACCAUUGUUUGGAGUUCAGUUUAACUGGCACAGUAAAGAAGGAGAUCCAUUAGUGUUUGCAACUGUAGGAAGCAACAGAGUUACCUUGUAUGAAUGUCAUUCACAAGGAGAAAUCCGGUUGUUGCAAUCUUACGUGGAUGCUGAUGCUGAUGAAAACUUUUACACUUGUGCAUGGACCUAUGAUAGCAAUACGAGCCAUCCUCUGCUGGCUGUAGCUGGAUCUAGAGGCAUAAUUAGGAUAAUAAAUCCUAUAACAAUGCAGUGUAUAAAGCACUAUGUUGGCCAUGGAAAUGCUAUCAAUGAGCUGAAAUUCCAUCCAAGAGAUCCAAAUCUUCUCCUGUCAGUAAGUAAAGAUCAUGCUUUACGAUUAUGGAAUAUCCAGACGGACACUCUGGUGGCAAUAUUUGGAGGCGUAGAAGGGCACAGAGAUGAAGUUCUAAGUGCUGAUUAUGAUCUUUUGGGUGAAAAAAUAAUGUCCUGUGGUAUGGAUCAUUCUCUUAAACUUUGGAGGAUCAAUUCAAAGAGAAUGAUGAAUGCAAUUAAGGAAUCUUAUGAUUAUAAUCCAAAUAAAACUAACAGGCCAUUUAUUUCUCAGAAAAUCCAUUUUCCUGAUUUUUCUACCAGAGACAUACAUAGGAAUUAUGUUGAUUGUGUGCGAUGGUUAGGCGAUUUGAUACUUUCUAAGAGUGGCCGUGCCAUUUUACAUUCCCACCAGCAAUGUAUGAGAGAUCCAGUGUCUCCGAAUCUUCGCCAGCAUUUGUCUUGUGAAAAUGCCAUUGUGUGCUGGAAACCUGGCAAGAUGGAAGAUGAUAUAGAUAAAAUUAAACCCAGUGAAUCUAAUGUGACUAUUCUUGGGCGAUUUGAUUACAGCCAGUGUGACAUUUGGUACAUGAGGUUUUCUAUGGAUUUCUGGCAAAAGAUGCUUGCAUUGGGCAAUCAAGUUGGCAAACUUUAUGUUUGGGAUUUAGAAGUAGAAGAUCCUCAUAAAGCCAAUCGUGACCACUGAUGUGCCAGUCUGCUUCAGUCUCUACCAAGCCCAGAACUUCACCCUCUAUCGGGUCCUGAGGAAAAGCAGCUUCCACGGUUUAUUUCAAGCUGGAUGAGGAUCCAAUUGAUGCCAUAUCCCUGUUGUAGCCUUUUGUGGUGAGACAAGGCGCUCAUCAGGACAGCAGAUUCUUCAAAGCCUUCCACACCAAUGUGAAGGACAGUAAGAUGUGGAAGUUCCUGGGUUUUGUUUUUGGACAAUGGGAACCAAGGGUGGCAUCCCUACACUCCAUAGUGUAGGGCCUGACACGAUGUAAACUCCCUCCUCCAGUAAUCAUUCAUCAAGAGUUUCAGUGUUGUGAUAACCUGUGAGUUCUCCACAUAGUGGCACAUCAUGGACCUCAUUUCCUUCCUGGAUUACAACUGCACCUUGGACAGUGAGGGCUCUUUUGGAAGUGCACACCUAGCUGACCUGCCCUCCAACUCAAAAGUGGACAAGACCUGUUCAGAGGUGUUAAGCACCCCCACACUCAAUGUCCAUUCAGGCCAAAAGUAUGCUCUUUGCCCCAAGGGAACCAAAGUCAUGAUGACAUAUGCCAGAGCUUGGGUAAAGGAUACAGUGAGGAUUCUUGGAUUUCAGAACAAAGUAUUCCUGGAGCCCCCUGUACUUCAUGAAGCCUAUGUCCAGCUUGUUGUCAAAGAAAUGUAGAUUAAUUCAAAAGGAACACAGGAUUCUAUCGGUCCUUUUCCUAGUCCUGAAGACAAGGUCAGCUAUGUAAUAUCCAGGGCCCAGUGCAAAAUGAAAAGGCAAACUCCUUGGGCCGGGUGCGGUGGUUCAUGCCUGUAGUCCCAGCACUUUGGGAGGCUGAGGUGGGCGGAUCAUCUGAGGUCAGGAGUUUGAGACAGCCUGGCCAACAUGGUGAAACCUCGUCUCUACCAAAAAUACAAAAGUUAGCUAGGCAUGAUGGCAUGUGCCUGUAAUCCCAGCUACUUGGGAGGAUGAAGCAUGAGAAUCACUUGAGCCCGUGAGGCAGAGGUUGCGGUGAGCUGAGAUUGUGCCACCACACUCCAGCCUGGGCAACAGAGUGAGACUCUGUCUCAAAAACGAAAAACCAAAAAACAGAAAAGGCUGGGCACGGUGGUUCAUGCCUGUAAUCGCAGCACUUUGGGAGGCCAAGGCAGGAGGACUGCUUGAGCCCAGGAGUUUGAGACCACCCUAAGCAACAUAGCAAGACGCUGUCUCUACAAAAUAUUUGAAAAUUAGCUGGGUGGAGUAGUGUGCACCUGUAGUCCCAGCUACUAGGGAGGCUAAGGUGGGAGUAUCACUUGAGCCCAGGAGGCUGAGGCUGCAGUGAGCUGUGAUCACACCACUGCAAUCCAGCCAGGGUGACAGAGCAAGACCCUGUCUCAAAAAAAGAAAAAAAAAUUAAAAGGAAAAAUUAGGUUAAAGGUACUAACUAUAAAGCUUUUUCCAUCCUUUAACAAUUUCUCAACUGGUCGUGGUUUUAAAUUUUGCUACUUAAUGCCAUUCUAAGUAAAGUAAAAUUGUUAGCAUGAAUUUUAUUAUUCAUUUUCAUAUUGUGUAAUGAUCAUUUUAUUUUUUUGAGACAGAGUUUCGCUCUUGUUGCCCGGGCUGGAGUGCAGGGGUGUGAUUUCAGCUCACUGCAACUUCCGCCUCCCAGUUUCAAGAGCUUCUCCUGCCUCAGCCUCCUGAGUAGCUGGGAUUACAGGCGUGCGCCACCAAGCCCAGCUAAUUUUUGUAUUUUUAGUAGAGACAGGGUUUCACCAUGUUGGCCAGGAUGGUCUCGAACUCCUGACCUCAAGUGAUCCAACCUGCCUCAGCCUCCCAAGGUGCUGGGAUUACAGGUGUGAGCCACCAGGCCUGGUGUAAUGAUCAUUUUAAAUACAAACAUAAGAGCCUUUACCUCUUAUGUGAAAUUAGAAAUUACAGAAUUGAUAUUUGUGUCUCAUACACACAAGUAUUUUGUUCUUACCAGGGGAGUGGAAACUCUGCACAAAAGUAACUCCACUUUUAUUUGAGACAGAGUCUCGCUCUGUCGCCCAGGCUGGAAUGCAGUGGUGCAAUCUCGGCUCACUGCAGCCUCCACCUCUCAGGUUCAAGCAAUUCUCCUGUCUCAGCCUCCUGAGUAGCUGGGAUUACAAAUGUGUGCCACCACAGCCAGCUAAUUUUUUUUUUUUUUGGUAUCGUUAGUAGAGACGGGGUUUCGCCAUGUUGGCCAGGCUGGUCUGGAACUCCUGGCCUCAAGUGAUCCGCCCGCCUCAGCCUCCCAAAGUGCUGGGAUUACAGGCGUGAGCCACUGUGCCUGGCUGAGAUGACAAAUAGGAUGAAGUCUUGGGGUGUUUCGAAGGAAAAAAAAUGGGGUGAGAAAGGAAUAAGAGGUGGCUUUGAGUAUAUCAUCUACUACAAAAUACUGGAAAAAGGCUGGUAGAAACUCAGUGACUUUAAAAUUAUCUUUAAGCAAAUGCCUGAGAAAGGCAAAAGUCUAAAGAAAUGAUGGUCACUUUUUCCAGAAGUGCUUAAAGAAUUGAAAUGCUCCUUUGAGGCAAAGGGGACAGUCAUUCUGCUUAAUUGCAUCUUCAGGCUUGAACAAGGUAUCAUCUAGGACAGUAGGUUUUAAAUUUUUUUUAAUGCAACCCACAGUAAGAAAUAGACUAUACAGGCCAGGUGCGGUGGCUCAGGCCUGUAAUCCCAGCACUUUGGGAGGCCGAGGCGGGCAGAUCACGAGGUCAGGAGAUCGAGACUAUCCUGGCUAACACGGUGAAACCCCGUCUCUACUAAAAAUACAAAAAAUUAGCCGGGCACGGUGGUGGGCACCUGUAGUCCCAGCUACUCGGGAGGCUGAGGCAGGAGAAUGGUGUGAACCCGGGAGGUGGAGCUUGCAGUGAGCCAAGAUAGCGCCACUGCACUCCUGCCUGGGCGAAAGAGCGAGACUCCGUCUCAAAAAAAAAAAAAAAAAAAAAAAGAAAUAGACUAUACAUAAUAACCCAAUCAUACACACAUAUAGAAAGUCCCAUGAAACAAUAUACUUACUAAUAUGAUGCAUUCUGAAAUUUUCUAUUUCUUUUUUUUUUUCUUUUUGUAAUGCUGGUUGUAACUCACUAAAUUGAUUUCACAACCUGCCCAUGGAUCUCAGCCUGCAGUGUGAAACACAGUAACCUAGGGAAAAUGAGUCUAGAUGGCUUUUACCAAGGGUAGUGGAAGUGGGGCCCACAUUGUGAGAAAUACAACCAUAAGUAAAAAGUGCUAAAUGGCCUCUCUUUAACCAGAGACCACAGUCUGUAACUUCCCCUGCUUUCAGUGGUUACCUCUGGGUUUCCCCUGUUGUGAUUUAUAGAAAAUGACUAUCACUUUGGAAUUGAGCUGGUGGAUUUCUACAAAGAUUCUUGGUAUUUCAUGGUUAUUUUCUGAUGUAGAGCAAGACUUCAUGUGAAUGAAAGCAGAUUCAUUUUGCCUUUCUUGCUUGGGUACCCCAGGCUGAUGUGGAAUAAAAAAUUGUUGGGUGAUUUCUCUUACAUUUCUGCAUAAUGAGUGAGGGAAGUGUGUGUGUUUAAUUCCGAAACCAAUAAACUGGGUUGCCAGAAAA